GGCGGGAUGGGUUUACAGGCUCCGUGAGAGGGCUGUAAGGAAGGAGAAUGAGUACAGGCAAUGCUAGAGUUUUCCUGAGGAGAGGAUGGUAUAGGAAAAGAAGUGGGUGAUGCUGGCUGGGAAGAUGGUGGCUGGGAAGAUGGUGGCUGAGAAGACAAUGAGGAAGCUUGGGGAGUUAAUGAAGUUGGUUGAGAUGGAGGGGUAGGGUCUGGGAGGGGUGGACAGCAGUCUGCUCCAUCCAAUGAGGAAAAAGAGGUAGGGUCGGGAGGAUAAAGGCAAUGAGGGCGGCGAGAAUGAAGAAGGAUUUGAACAGAUAUAAGUAUGAGAAAUGACAGAAAGAAACAACAACUGGAAAAGAAGCAUUGCAUAAGACCAGGAUGUCUCUGAAAUGGACGUCAGUCUUUCUGCUGAUACAGCUCAGUUGUUACUUUAGCUCUGGAAGCUGUGGAAAGGUGCUAGUGUGGCCCACAGAAUACAGCCAUUGGAUAAAUAUGAAGACAAUCCUGGAAGAGCUUGUUCAGAGGGGUCAUGAGGUGACUGUGUUGACAUCUUCGGCUUCUACUCUUGUCAAUGCCAGUAAAUCAUCUGCUAUUAAAUUAGAAGUUUAUCCUACAUCUUUAACUAAAAAUGAUUUGGAAGAUUCUCUUCUGAAAAUUCUCGAUAGAUGGAUAUAUGGUGUUUCAAAAAAUACAUUUUGGUCAUAUUUUUCACAAUUACAAGAAUUGUGUUGGGAAUAUUAUGACUACAGUAACAAGCUCUGUAAAGAUGCAGUUUUGAAUAAGAAACUUAUGAUGAAACUACAAGAGUCAAAGUUUGAUGUCAUUCUGGCAGAUGCCCUUAAUCCCUGUGGUGAGCUACUGGCUGAACUAUUUAACAUACCCUUUCUGUACAGUCUUCGAUUCUCUGUUGGCUACACAUUUGAGAAGAAUGGUGGAGGAUUUCUGUUCCCUCCUUCCUAUGUACCUGUUGUUAUGUCAGAAUUAAGUGAUCAAAUGAUUUUCAUGGAGAGGAUAAAAAAUAUGAUACAUAUGCUUUAUUUUGACUUUUGGUUUCAAAUUUAUGAUCUGAAGAAGUGGGACCAGUUUUAUAGUGAAGUUCUAGGAAGACCCACUACAUUAUUUGAGACAAUGGGGAAAGCUGAAAUGUGGCUCAUUCGAACCUAUUGGGAUUUUGAAUUUCCUCGCCCAUUCUUACCAAAUGUUGAUUUUGUUGGAGGACUUCACUGUAAACCAGCCAAACCCCUGCCUAAGGAAAUGGAAGAGUUUGUGCAGAGCUCUGGAGAAAAUGGUAUUGUGGUGUUUUCUCUGGGGUCGAUGAUCAGUAACAUGUCAGAAGAAAGUGCCAACAUGAUUGCAUCAGCCCUUGCCCAGAUCCCACAAAAGGUUCUAUGGAGAUUUGAUGGCAAGAAGCCAAAUACUUUAGGUUCCAAUACUCGACUGUACAAGUGGUUACCCCAGAAUGACCUUCUUGGUCAUCCCAAAACCAAAGCUUUUAUAACUCAUGGUGGAACCAAUGGCAUCUAUGAGGCGAUCUACCAUGGGAUCCCUAUGGUGGGCAUUCCCUUGUUUGCGGAUCAACAUGAUAACAUUGCUCACAUGAAAGCCAAGGGAGCAGCCCUCAGUGUGGACAUCAGGACCAUGUCAAGUAGAGAUUUGCUCAAUGCAUUGAAGUCAGUCAUUAAUGACCCUGUCUAUAAAGAGAAUGUCAUGAAAUUAUCAAGAAUUCAUCAUGACCAACCAAUGAAGCCCCUGGAUCGAGCAGUCUUCUGGAUUGAGUUUGUCAUGCGCCACAAAGGAGCCAAGCACCUUCGAGUCGCAGCUCACAACCUCACCUGGAUCCAGUACCACUCUUUGGAUGUGAUAGCAUUCCUGCUGGCCUGCGUGGCAACUGUGAUAUUUAUCAUCACAAAAUUUUGCCUGUUUUGUUUCCGAAAGCUUGCCAAAAAAGGAAAGAAGAAGAAAAGAGAUUAGUUAUAUCAAAAGCCUGAAGUGGAAUGACUGAAAGAUGGGACUCCUCCUUUAUUUCAGCAUGGAGGGUUUUAAAUGGAGGAUUUCCUUUUUCCUGUGACAAAACAUCUUUUCACAACUUACCUUGUUAAGACAAAAUUUAUUUUCCAGGGAUUUAAUACGUACUUUAGCUGGAAUUAUUCUAUGUCAAUGAUUUUUAAGCUAUGAAAAAUACAAUGGGGGGAAGGAUAGCAUUUGGAGAUAUACCUAAUGUUAAAUGACGAGUUACUGGAUGCAGCACGCCAACAUGGCACAUGUAUACAUAUGUAGCUAACCUGCACGUUGUGCACAUGUACCCUAAAACUUAAAGUAUAAUUUAAAAAAAGCAAAAAAAAAAAAAUACAACUCUUUUUUUUAAACCAGGAAGGAAAAUGUGAACAUGGAAACAACUUCUAGUAUUGGAUCUGAAAAUAAAGUGUCAUCCAAGCCAUAAAAAAAAAAGAAAAGAAAAAUAAAAAUAAUAUAAAACCUUA